AGACAAGGUCAUCUAUGCUGGAGUGCAGUGGCGUGCUCUCGGCUCACUGCAACCUCCACCUCCCGGGUUCAAGCAAUUCUCAUCUCACCUUCCUGAGUAUCUGGAGUUGCAGCGUGAGCCACUGCGCCUGGCUAAUUGUUUUGUAUUUUUAUUAGAGUUAGGGUUUCACCAUGUUUGCCCGGCUGGUCGCAAACUCCCGGCUCCAAGUGAUCCGCCCGCCUUGGCCCCCAAAGUGCUGGGCUUGCAGAUGUGAGCUACUGUGCGCAGCCUUUAUAAACAAUUUUGAUAUAUGGUGAAAUUUCUCAAAGCUUGCUGAUCAUAGUGAAUUAUGCUGAUAAGAAUGGGAAACAAGAUUAUUGGGAAUAAAUUGAAAAAUAUUAAAUAGGUUUUUAUGCGUCAAGGGUAAAAAAAAUGUGUUUUGAGUAAAUGAUCUGAAAUACAGCAUGCUUUUUUGGUAAAAGCUUAGUAUAAUGUAGGGUGAAGUUAAGGCGUUGGCGAUAACCAGAAUCAUAAUUCUCAUUUUAAAUAAUGCUAUGCUACAUCUGCACAAAAUAGAUUAUGUAUAUUUUUGGCUGCUGUACCAUGAAAAUGAUGACUAAAACGAGGUCUAGAGAGGGAUAGUUUAAAAAUGAUGGUAGGGCUAGAGAUGGAAUCCAUGAUUGAGGAGGACUGUAGAUUUUACUUAACUAUAUUCUUUCUUUUUAAUUUAUUUUUAUUUUAUUUUAUUUUUUUUGAGACGAAGUCUCGCUCUGUCUCCCAGGCUGGAGUGCAGUGGCGCCAUGCCGUCUCACUGCAACCUCCGCAUUCCAGAUUCAAGUGAUUCUUCUGCCUCAGCCUCCCAGGUAGCUGGGGCUACAGGCGCCGGCGCCACCACGCCCGGCUAAUUUUUGUAUUUUUAGUAGAGACGAAGUUUCACCAUGUUAGUCAGGCUGGUCUCGAACUCCUGACCUUGGAUCCGCCCCCCUCGGCCUUCCAAAGUGCUGGGAUUAUAGGCGUGAGCCACAGCACCCGGCCGAUUUUACUUAAGUAUAUUCUUAUUGCUUAUUACUUCAUACUCAAACUGACUUAUAAGGUAGAGAAAAUCAUAAUGUGUACCAGAUAGUGCUAUUUCAGUUUAGAAAAUAAAUUCAUUUUUUAUUUCUUGAGAUUAUUUGAAAGUACAUUGUAGAAAUGGCACAUUUAUGGAACUGCUUUAUGGCUGUGCCUCUCUUGCAGGGAAUUUUGCCUCCCCCUUUCCUUUUCCCAAAAAUACUAUUAGCUUGCCUAAUUUAACCUUUCACUUUUUUUAUCCCCAUCUUCCCCCACAAAAGAAAGGAAUAGAAAAGAAAAAUACGAAAGUGAAGAAAUAAGAACCUGCUCUAAAGUUAUUUCUUGGUCUGGGUUUCUUUAUGGAUCAUCUCUUAAUUAGCUUAAAAACAUUUGAUUGAAACCUAUUUUGGAAGUAUCUAUGGAAAGGUUGGUUCCAUUAGUUUGGAAUUUAGAAUAAAUAUAUGUUACCAUAGAGAUCUAUUUUCCUUUCCCUCUUUUCCUGUCAACCUAAAUGUGAAGAUUGACAAGAAAAGGAAGCCCACCUGUUUGUGUUACAGUUAGUGUUAGAAAUGCCUUUGACCCCAUUGUUGUCUCUUUCUUUCUCUGUGCCAUGUUUAUUUUUUUAAUGGCAUUAAUAAUGAAAACAGUCUUGUUUCAAAGCCUCUAGUAUAGCACAUACUAGAAUUAACUCCUACAGGAGUUAAUUCUUUUACCUGACAAACAUUUAUUAUCUCCUAUGUGUGGCUGUUUUCAUUGUCUAAUCUGAACUAUUUCCUUCCCAGUGAAUAUGAAAAAAAAUUAUAUUUAAAAUUAUAGCUGUAUAUGUUAAAUAUGAAUAAGUUAAUUUGUACAUAUUGUAGUUAGUAAAACUUACAUACAUUGAAACUUAGCACAAUGAUAGAAUUCAGUUUUCCACGUGAUUAUUAGCUAUUAUCUAAUCUUAUUAGCUAUGAUUAUUAGCUAAUAGUUUUAUCACUAUUAGUAUACUCUCUGAACUAAAUUUAUUUAAGAAGCAUUAUUAACAUCUAGCAAAAUUACCUAGGUAUUAUAAGGGUUUUGAAGAAAUGGGGACAUUAUUUCUAGAUUCAUAAAAUUUAAAUUUUGUUGAGAUAAAACUAGUAAUAAUUUAAAACUGUGAAGAUGAUUUUAGCCCCGUAUAAAUCCUAUACUUUUUUGGGGCAUCUAUGUUCAUUUUUGGUGUAACUGUGUGCCUUAUGAUCAUAGGGAUCAUUUUGUUUUGGUUUUUGAAUACUAGUAGGGUAGACUUUAUAUCUUUUAUGAGUGUCUCCUGGAAUACUCAGUGAUUUUUGAUAUUUUGUUUGUUCUUAAGAUGAGGUCUGUAUGUACGAUUUUUCUAGAGUGUCCUUGACAACUAGAUUAUACUAAAGAGUCAUCCAUUCUAAUUUUACCUUGAAGGUUUUAUAGUAAGAAAGGAGAGUAUCUAUAUUAAUAUACUUGUGAUUGAUGCAGGUGGAGAUAUGUUAAAAUAUGAAGAUUGAAUUACAAGACAGUGUAGGAUGAAAAUUCUUAAGAUUUUAAAUAUAGCGUUACAUAUAAUUAAAUGUUAUUCAUUAAUUUAUACCUAUUUGUAGAAACACAUAUUUGCAGAAAACUUGACAAACUCAAAAAGAUCUAAAGAAUAGAAAAAUCACCUAUUAUUCUGUCUUCAGAAUUAAUCAUUACCUGAAAUACGUCUUUUCAUUCUUUUUCCUUGUUAUGUUGUAGUGAAAUUAUCACAAAGAGCAGAGGUACCACUUAGAAAUUUUGCUUGCUGAAAUUUUUAUUGAUGAGCUUUCUUCAAAUAUAUCAAUUGAAGAGAUGAGUCUUCAGAUUAUGAUUUUUAUAUAUUUAAAAAUAAAAACUAAUGACGGUAUUUAUACUUACAAAAAUGUCUUCUAGUAUAUAGGGCUUUUUAUUCCAUUCUUAGAGUAAAUGCUGCUAACAGUUGGUGUAUAUCAAAUGUUUGUUUCUUUCUUGAGACUGAGUGCGUGUGUGUGUGUGUUAGAGUAUGUUAAUAUUUGCCACAUUAUUCUCAUUUACUUAUGAAUGUUCCAUAAUAUAAAUGUUCAUAAUUUAUUUGAUCUUUUAUUUUGGUAGACAUUUAGAUUGUUUUCACUACAUUGCUAUUAGUGAAGUGAACAUCCUUGUACAGUUAUUUUUGAGUAUGAAACUAUUUCUUUGGGAUGGAUUCCUGGAAAUGGAAUUGUUGGGCUAGAGUAUGCACAUGUUAAAUUUGAUAAAUACUCUCAAGUUUUGCUUGCAUCAGCAGUGUAUGAGAAUGUUCCUAGAUGUGGUUAAUUUACUUAGUUUUAAAAAUCUGUUAAACAAAAAAUGGUGUUUUGUUUUCAUUUUUCUGAUUACUGUCAACAUUGAGUAUAAGUUUUUUAAUCUUUGUUUUUCAUUUGGAUGUCUUGAAAAUUUCCUGGUUUAUCCUUUACCUAUUUUUCUAUUAGGAUUGUCUUGUUGUUUUCUUAUUGAUUUGUUGAUAGUAUUUAUAGUAUUAAUUUUUCAUAGUGUUAUGUGUUACAGUAUUCUCCCUUGACAUUGUUUUCACAACAUGGAAAAAUUUAUUGUUUAGUAAAAUGUAUUAUUCUUUUAUGACUUCUGGAGAACUUCCUCACUCCAGUAUUUAACAAUUCUUAGAAAUUUUUCUUUGUACUUUGUUUUUCAAAGAUACAUGGAUCUCUUUUUGGAUAUAGUAUUUAAUUCUUGUGUCUGUUUCUUAUUUACUCCUUUUUAUAGCAGUUGACUGAUUCUUGCUUCUUAAAAUGUAAUCCUCUCUUCCUCAUGUAAUACCACCUUCUCCUGUUUGUACCUCACUGUUUUUUGUUGGUCAUCUUGCUUCCUUUUACCCCGCACAGCAAACAUACUUUGAUUAUUUACCUCAUUGGACCCUUUUCUGUUUUGUGUCUGGUCUCAUUUAGAUGAUUUUAACUAUUGUGUCGUUACAUAUCUAUAUACCAGUGACUAUCAGGUUUACAGCUCCAACCUAAACCUUUGUUUUUUUUGAGAAUUGGGCUCACCCUUCUGGCCACCUACCAUUUGUGCAAACCUUUCUUCCAACACCUAAUUGUUUCUUUCCUCAAGAGAAUCAAUUCAAAGUCCCAUCCAGUUACUACAUACAGCUCCAAGUGAAAGAUAUAUACAAAAUGCUUUUCCUCCUAAUUCAGAGAAUUCUAGUGAUCUAUAAAGCAAUAAACAACUAUCUCUCCCUCUUUUCACCCAACCCAUUGUGUAGUAGUGAGUAGGAAUAGGAUAAUCAUAAUGAAAACUCUUCUAGAGAAGGGAAGAAUAGGAAGUACACAGCAGUCAUUGGUACAUAUUAAUAAUGAAAUCCUUCGGGGGAGGAGUUGUGACAACUUUGCUCUGGCUACUGAGUAAUUUUCUUGGUUAUACUGAUUUUCCUCUAUGAGAGGAAUGCUCUUUUCACUGCUGUCUGUUUCCUUUGCUUAGUUCUUUAGAUGAUUCUUUCUUGUUUGUUAUCUUCCUUAGCCACAUUUGAAGUAGUAGGCAUUGGAGGGUGUGACAUCCCUAGGAAGUGUACAACUUUUGUAGCCCCCUACCUGUUGGUAUAGAUGCAGGGCCGGUAGGGUUACUUAAAGUUCAAGUGUAAGAUUUUUAGGCCAGUAAUGUAGUUUGUUGGUAAAACUCUUUCAAAAACAUAAUAGAUUUCUUUUCUGUUUUUCUUAGAUCGGGACUAUGUAACAAUAACUAUAGCAAAAUAUCUCUUAGUCCUAAGUUUUGGAAACCAGCUGAUUCUCUUAUUUACUGGUCUCUGUGCUAGGCUAGCUCCUCUCUCCCUUAGGUUUCCUGGCUACCUCGAGAGGAUCUGAAAUAAUAGUCUUGGAUGAUGUAUCAGUAAGGGUUUAACCAGAGAAGCAGAGCAAGUAGAUUUAUAUAUGAUUGUUAUGUAUUAAGAGAUUUAUUACAAGGAAUUUGGCUUACAUGAUUGUGAGGGCUGGCUAAGCAAGUGUGAAAUCUGUACGGCAGGCAGUUAGUGGGAGAAGAUUGUGGGCAAGGUGGAAUCCAUGGGCUUAGGCUGAAGCUGUUCUCCAUAGGCAGUCAGGAAGGGAAGAUACAGCGAAGAGAGAACAAUUGUAGACUCAGCUGCUGUUUGGAGUCUCAUUUGCUCGGAAGAACCUGAUCUCUUUUAAGAGCUCACCUGACUAGGUCAGGCUCACUGAGGAUGAUCACCCUGGCUUAAAGUCAGUUGAUUAGGAACUUCAAUUACAUCUGCAAAAUCCCCUCACAGCAGUACCUAGAUUAGCAUUUGACUGAAUAAUUGAGAGAAGGUAUUUGUGCUACAAAAUGUCUGCUGUCCUGUCUUCUUUCUAAGAAGAAACCAUUACAGGUGGAAAAGCAACACUCUUAACUUGAUCUUUGCUACUACCUGACAGAGAACCCUUGAACUCACAAAGUUAUUUCCUGGUAUUUAGAGCACAGAAGCAGCUGCCUUUUCCAUCCUGGGAGGCCCCAAAUUACUGGACUCUUGUAGGUCGGAGUUUGCCACUGAGAAAGCUUCUUUUUAGUAGCACUGUUUUCAUGUCUGUCUCUGCUUGCAAACUGCUUUAUAGGUGAAUUGAUCUUUCUUGUUGAUCUUUAAAUAGCCAACACACCAUAUUUCGAGUUUUUCUAACUGCUUUUCUUAGAACUACAAACUUAGUAGGCAUAUGAUGUGCCCUUCCAAUUAUUGCAGGCAAGAGUUUUACUAAAUGUUCUGCAACUGUAUAGCACAGAUCAUUAGAUCUCCAGCCUGAGAUGUUUCCUUGCUACCUGUUCUCUAAGCCUUACCAGAGAUUUUAGGAGUUUGUUAGAGCAGCGUGUCAUUUCCAAUUAACUGUAUUAGUUAAGGUAUAGGAUGGAUCAUUUGAACAAAGAGACUCCAGAACACAUCAGGCAAGAUAGAAGUUUGUUAUUCUUUUAUGUGCUACUCCAGAGGUAGACCUUCAGGUUAUUCACACAUCUAAGUAUCUGCUGUCUUGCACUUGAUACACCAUCCCUUAAUCAGUGCUGUCCAAUACUGUAGCCACUAGCCACAGGUUGCUGCUGAGCUCUUGAAAUGUGGCUAGCGCAUCUAAGGAUUUGAGUUAAAUUUUUUUUAAUUUUUAAUUUAAAUAUUACAUGUAGCUAGUGGCUACCAUAUUGGAGAGUGCAUAUGUAGAAUAUUUCCAUCACAGAAAGUUUUAUUGGACAGCUCUGCUUUGGAGUGUUCAUCUACAAGAUCUACUGUGGCUCACUAGCAUCAUGUCCAUGUUUCAGCCUGUUAUGGGCUGAACUGUGUGUCCCCAACAUUAAUAUUAAUAUUUUGAAGCCCUAACCCCAAGUAUUUCAGAAUGUGAUUGUACUUGGAGAUAAGUCCUUUAAAAAUGUAAUUAAGGUUCAAUCAGGUCAUAUGAGUGGGCCUUAAUCCAUCUGACUGAUGUACUUAUAAAAAGAGGACAUUUGAACACAGGACACCGGAGAUACAUGCCCACAGAGAAAAGGCCAUGUGGGGAUACAGCAAGAAGGUGGUCAUCUGUAAGCCAAGGAGAGAGGCCUCAGGAGAAACAAAUCUGCAGACACCCAGAUCUUGGACUUACAGUCUCCAGAACUGUGAGAAAAUAAAUAUCUGUUGUUUAAACUACCCAGUCUAUGGUAUUUUGUUAUGGUAGCGCUAGUAAACUAAUACUGGAGAAAUAAGAAACAGAAAGGUCAGCAUAGGUAACUUCCUUUUGAGGAAUUGACCAACAAGUUGCCAACGUCAUUUUCCAUUAUAUCCCAUUGACCAGAAAUUUCUUACGCAGCCAUAUCUAAGACUCAGCUCUUGCUGAGUGGCCAUGUACCCAGGUAAAACUUGUGGAGAAGUAGUCUUUUGCUAAAAGAAGGGGACUGUGGAUAUUGGAGGGUAAUUAAUGUUUUAUAUUGAUACAAUUCUAUGAUUAUAUUGUCCUUAUGACUACCAAAACAAGAAUGAAAGUCAUUCCUGGUUCCUGAAAUAAUCUUGUGGGCCAAGCUUUGGUCAUGUGUCCAUUCUUGAACCAGCCACUAUCACUAAGGAAAAAGAUGCUUUGUUUAGGACUAGGUCAUGUUUCUCCACCCUAUGUAGGAGGUAGACUAGGAGAGGUCCAUUCUACCUCCAAAAUAUGUCUUGAAUUUUUCUCCUUCUCUCCUUCUCCACUACCAUCGCCUUAACCCUGGCUAUUUUCUUACUUGAACUUCAUAGUAGCCUCCUAAUUUGAUCUCCUGGCUUUUUCUCCUGAAUCCCCAUUCUUCAUUCAUUCUUCACGUAGCAUUAGGCUAAUCUUUCUGAAAUGUCAUUGUUAUUUGAUUUCUCAUUGCUUUUAGAAUAAAAUCCAAACUCCUAACUUGCCCCACAGAACUUUGUAUGGCUGCUCCUUGUUGUUCCAGCCCUUCUAGUUCCUUGACUGUCGUCUAGUAGCACUGACCCUCCUUGUUUUGAAACAUGCAGACUUUCUAGCUAGGGUCUUUUUACUUUCUUCCUAGUGUGGUGUUCCCCUGGUUCUUUGUUUUUUCUCAUCCUUUAGUUUUCAGCUUAGAUAUCCUUCUUCGUCCAGUAUUGUUAGAGGGAACUUUCUCCCCUUACACCACUUCUUCUUUUACCUCCCUUUUAGUUUUUUGCCUUAACUGAGUAAGUUGCACUGUAGUGAAACAUAGGAAAGAGCCCUGUUGGUUUUUCACCAAGCUUUAUUAGUAUUAAAUAUUUAGUAAACUCUUAUGUCUGUUUCUUACUACGUGGAAAGAAGUUUGUGGGUGGAAGUGGGGUGGGAGACUUUGAGUGAAUUUCACAGUUGAACCUUGGCGAAAUUAUUUUUAUAAGCCACAAGUCAUUGAAUAUCUGGUUUCAUAUGAUUCAGCCUAAUAUGUUAGCAUGGUUUGGUAUCUUAGAAGGCAGUUCUCACUCAUUGAGCUUCUUUCUCAAGAGUUUUGGAUAUUGUUCAUUUAACAUGUCAGACAUGCUUUAGAAUCAUCUUUUGUACGUGACCAUGAAAUAUUCUCAGAUUAUACAUUGAAAUUUGUGUUAAUUUUGGAGAGAAAUAUAUGUAUAAUACUGAAUAUUCCCAUUCGGAAACAUGGCAUACUUAUGUAUUUUCAGGCCCUUCAUCUGUCUUUAAUAAAAUUUUAGUUUUUGUAUAGAUUUUACACAUUUCUUGUGGAAUUUAUUUCAGAUUAUUUUAUAGUUCUUCCUGCUAUCAUGUAUGGUAUAUUUUAUUCCAUUAUACUUUCUUAAUUAGUUAUUGUUGGAAUAUAGGAAGCUAUUGAUUGGCAUAUUUUAAUCUUGUAUAUGGCCACUAAACUGAAUUCUUGUAUUCAGUUUAUUCUGUUGAAUUUUCUGACUCAAAUGUCAUAUUGAUUCCAGUAAAUUAUUUUUUCUCUCAUUUCCAGUAUUUGUCCCUUGUGUUUGUUUUUGUUCUCUUAUUGCGUGAGUUUUGAACCACCCCCAAAAUGUUGAAUGUCAGUGGUAACAGAGGUUAUACUUGUCUUUCUCUUAUUUUUAAUGGAAGUGCUGUUGUUUUACUACUAAGUAUAAUGCAGAUAUCUUUUAUCAAUUUAGGGUACAUCACUUUUUCUUAAAUUACUUAAGUUUUAUUAGAAAUAAUGUACUAAAUUUUAUCAAAUGCAUUUUUGGCAUCUUUUGAAAUGGUCAGUUCUUUUUCUGCCCCUUCAGUAUGUCCAUAUGGUGAAUUGUAAUAAAAGAUUUCCUAAUUUUAAUUGUGUUUUGAAUACUUGGUAUGAUGAAUUAUUUUAAUGCACUGUUGGUUUAGUUUCAUUAAUAUUUUAAUUUAUAUUUUCUAUGAAGAUUAUUCAUGUUAGUUUUUCAAAUUUAUUUGAAGAAACUGUAAAUAUUUUUUCCUUACAUCAGUUUUGUAAAGAUACUCAUUUUACAGAUUCAGUUUAUGUGCAUCCUUUUUCCUUUUAGUCUUAUAUGUUGUGUUUUUAACCUUAUUGGCCACUGAAAUGUUAGAAAGAAGUUAGAGUAAGUGGUUUAUUUGAUCUUUUUAUAGUUUAGUAAUUUUUUAAAAAGUGGCUUUAAGUAAUUUAGUACAUACCUCUUUUUAAAAAUAAUAACUUACUAGUUAGUUAAUAUACUAUUCUCGAGGUUCAUUUAUGUUGUAGCAUGUGACUGGAUUUCCUUUUAAAUAUUCCAUUGUAUGUAUAGAUCACAUUUUAUUUAUCCAUUCAUUAGUUAAUGGACCGUUUGGGUUGCUUCCAUCUCUUGGCUAGUGUGCCUCUUAACUUUUACAUUUUAUUCAUUUAUUUCAAAUUUAUAUGGGUUCAUUGAGGGGAAUAGGAACUUAAUCUUGUAUUUCCAAAUAGUUAAUCAGUUGACUUAUCUGUUUCAUAGUCUGUCCUCAUUAUUUGAAUAAUGCCUUUAUUUUAUGUAUUUCCACAAUACAACAAUAAACCAAAUAUCUGCUCAGUAUAUACAUCUUUAUAAGUACUGAAUUUGGGCCGGGCACGGUGGCUCACAUCUGUAAUCCUAGCACUUUGGGAAGCCGAGGUGGGCGGGUUGCCUGAGCUCAGGAGUUCAAGACCAGCCUGGGGAACAUGGUGAAACCCCGUCUCUAUUAAAAUACAAAAAAAAUUAGCUGGGUGUGGUGGCAUGCUCCUGUAGUCCCAGCUACUCGGGAGGCUGAGGCAGGAGAAUUGCUUGAACCCGGGAGGCGGAGGUUGCAGUGAGCCGAGAUUGUGCCACUGCACGCCAACCUGGGUGUCAGAGCAAGACUCAUCUCCAAAAAAAAAAAAAAAAAAAAGAAUAAGUACUGAAUUUAUAUAAGCUGAAGGCCUGAAUACUAAAAUUGGCUACUUGUACUAAGCAGUUUCCUGUGUUUGUUAAGUAGCUAACAUCUGUGUGGGGUUUUAUGGUUAAAGGAAUUUUAGAUGUUUUCCACUUAAUCAAGUCAGUUAUGUGUUUUUUUAAAUUCUAAUUUUUUUAGGCACAGGGUCUUGCUCUGUUGCAUAGGCUGGAGGGCAGUGGCAUGAUCAUAGCUCACUGCCGCCUCGAAAUCCUGGGCUCAAGUGUUCCUCCCACCUCAGCCUCCCAAGUAUCUGGGACUACAGGUGCAUGCCACCAUGCCUAGCUAAUUUUUUUUUUUUUUUUUGUAGAGAUAGUCUUGCUGUGUUGCCCAAGUUAUUCUAGAACUCCUGGGCUCAGGUGAUCCUCCUGCCUUGGCCUCUCAAAGUGCUAGUAUUCCAGGCAUGAGCCCAUGUGCCCAGCCAAGUCAGUGAUCUUUUGAAGCAAUUUUUCUUCUUUUAUUGCUUAAACCUCUAAACAGGCUUGACAUUUUUUUUUCUUUUCUCUUUCCCUCCCUUACAGAUUCUAGUACAGAAGUACUUUUAUGAAGAAAAUAUAAGCAAUGCCAGCAUCUAUAUAGUGUUCUUACUGAUUUGAUGAUGCCCUUAGGUUGUCUUUGAACUUGAAAAUCUCUAUACAUUAUUAUUGCAGGACCUAUAAACUAUGACUGUUGUGUAGUUCUCUUGCACUAUCUUUCCAAUGUUCUUUGAAGAACUGUUUCACUGUUUAUUUUAUCUAUUUCAAAUGAACUAGGAGUAAUUUAAAACUUACAUAGUUGCUGUUCAGAAAAUGUCAAAAAAGAAGAGCUUGUAUAAGAUACAAUGUAGAUAAAUUUAAUUCUAUUGAGGGGGUAAUAUCCUUUUAAGAUACAAUGUAGAUAAAUUUAAUUCUAUUGAGGGGGUAAUAUCCUUUAAACCAAACUUGUCUAAAGUUUUCACCAAAUGUUAAACUGUGAGUAAUGUUUUCUUUUUAUUUAUCCAUUUGAUUUUUUUAUAUUGGAGGAAUCUUAAAAUUGCAGUAUCUUUUUCCACUUUUAUUAAAUCAUAUAGUAACUGUGAACUGAAAAUUUAAACAGUAGAGGAAGAUACAGAGUAAGAGUUGAAGAUUUUUUAUAUCCCUAGGUGUAAAUUGUAAGUGUAUGUAAUCCUAUGCCUUUUUCUGUGCAUUUUCACACAUAUACAGAUAUAUCUAUGUAAUUUUGUUUUGCAUAAAUGAGAUCAUUAUAAAAAUAUUGUUUGAAACUUUCUUUUUAAAUUAAUAUUCCAUCAUAGAUUUUCACGUUAAUACACAUAUAGUUAUCUUAGUCCUUUAAAUGGCUGUGAGUAUUCCCUUGUCAGGUAUCAGGACUUAAUUGCUUUCCAGUUUAUGGAAAUUUUGGUUGUAUCCAAAGUUCUGCUGUUACAAACAAUACUGAAGUGGACUUUUUGAUAUUGUUUCUGUAUUGUGGUAAGAUAUAUUCCAGAGGUAAAACUGCUAGACCAAAGGUAUGGGAAUCUAUUUCUGUAACUGACAUUUUAUUGUGUGUCAGCACUGUAUUUUAAAAACUAGUGAUUUUGUAGUGGUAUAGGAUCUGAUAGGUCAAACAUCAGCUUUCAAGCCCUGUUCAUCUCUGUUCUUUCUGGAUAUCCCUCUCUGUUGACUACUUUAUCCAUAAAAGGGCCAGAUCAUAUAUCACCUCUUUCCUGAAGGUGUUUAUAACACCUAGAACAUUGAAUAAUUUUAACCCCAGUAAUAGUUUAGUGAGUGCUUACUGUGUGCCAGCCACAAUUCUAAUUGGUUUAUGUGUAUUACACUGCUGUAUAUCAUUUAAUCUUCCCAGUUCUAAGAGGUACAUAGUAUCUACACUUUGUAGUUGAAAAAAUCAAGGUAAAGAAUAAGUAACUUGUUCAAGGUCACAGUAAGUGAUGGAAAUGGAAUAUAAACAUGGGUAGUCUCACAUGAAAGUCUGCUUUCUUAACUCUCAUAUUGUACUGCCUUCUUACCAUCCUUUUAUGGCCUCCCUAGUAAUUGCUCAAGAAAUAUGUUUUGUAUGCAUUGUAGAGUUCACUAGCCAUUUCAUCUUGCUUCUAAGUCCUCUUUACAGAUCUGUAUGAAUACCGUCUUACUCAAAUUUAUGUAUAGUGACCUAUCCCCAAGUAGGAUAACCAGAGAGAAAUGAUGGAGUAAGGAGGGUUAUGGAAGACCUCCUUACUCCAAAACACUUUACCUGAAUGUAGCUAGUUAAUACUGCUCUGUUUUAUUUCAUCUUGUUUCCCUAACUCCUGUCUUGGGAACAUUCAUGGAUUAAUCUUGGGAUGGAUUUCAUAGGUGGAAUAAAUGGGAAUGUCACUCUUCAAUAUUUCUGAAACAUCAAAUCAAAAUACAUACCUUGUAGAUUACCUCUUACAGUAAGUGCUCAAAAUGUGAAGUGGGAAGAAUGCUGUUUUAGACCCUCCUAUACCUCUUAAUUCAUGCUGUUAGGUAAGUGUGACAUGUAAAAAUUAAAUAUCUCAGUCUCUCAUAAAAGGGGCCUGGUAAUACUUUCUUUUGAGGGAGGUUAGGUGACCUAAUGUUUGUGAAAAUAUUUGUGACCUAUAAGGAUUUUCAUAAAUUAAUUGUUAAAACUGAAGUAUGAAUAAAAAUAGAGAGUCUUAUGAAAAUUCUGACUACUGAGAUGGUUGGUUUUUUUUUUUUUUAAUUUAGGAGAAUCCCUUAUUUUAAAUUUCUAAUUCUAUUAAAUUUGGUUAUCUUAUUGAAUUUAUAGAUUGCUAGUAAAUAUUUUCAGUUCUAAUUGUACAUUUUGGUUAAUUGUUUUAGGUGGAGCUGAUAGUAGAUAGGUUAAGGGGUUGGGAUUCUGUAAUGAACAGUUCACAAAAUAAUGGUUGUAUUCUGAAUUUGUUAAGUUUUUAGAAUUUAUGUAGAAUAUGUUCUUAAAUUCCUUGAGAACUUAAAAAUUUGUAGUACUUUAUCAUACUGUUAAUAAAGAGGGAGAGAUAAGGGUUAUGGGAAAUGCACAUCCUUUUCUGACUCUUAAGUCCUUUUCUGGGAAUAUGAAAGCAAACCAUAUGCCUAUGGCGUCUCUGCUAUAGGCUUAGCAGAUAAUACUAGGGUUCUAGAUAAAAUGAAAAGUAUGAAGGCAAAGAUUUGAUCAUGCUGUUUUCUAAAUCUCAGGACCUUUAGAAUGUAUCUCUAACUCACUUUGUGGACUCCUUUCACUUGUACCUUUUCUUCCUUUUCUUACUCUGCAUCCAGAUCCCCACCUCACAGUCCAAGAUCCUCUCUACCACUCAGUCCAGCUUUCUGGCUGCCACCUAAACUUCAGUACCUGGCUUCUCUUGGCCAGAUCGAAGGACUGUAAUAUGAUUUAAGUUGUGAAUAUGCCUUAGUAUGUGAGAUGUCUUUUCAUAUGAGGGAGUUCUUAACCUACUUUAGCUUAAUCACCAGAUCCUUUUGUCUUUUAUGCUAACACAUAAAAAACACAGGCUUGGUAUUACAGCUUUUUGUCUUCUAUGCAUGAGCAGUUUUGUUUUGUAUCCCAGGGAUCCCAGAAGAACAGCUUUGCUUGGCCAGGGUACCCAUUCAUUGGCUUAGGCAACCUAGAAUGUUAAGAUUCAUAUAUCUUAAUCAAAUACGAAGGUCUUCCUGACCUCACUACCAUAAGCAGAAGUUUUUCUGAAAACUUUGAUCAGAGAGCAAGUAGGAAGAAGGGCCAGAUUCCAGUUUCAUUAAACCACAGGCAUAUGAAUACUUCACAGUUUCUGUGCUUGACAAAAAUUACAUUUAAUUCUGAAAUAACCCAAUGCCUUUGUAUUUCUUUUCUUACACUAUUUCUCCAGGAAAAAAGCAUGAUAUGGAAAGAGUUUGAAAUCAAGUUGAGCCACUUGCUUUUGAAUCCUGCUUUAACACUGUGUGAUUUGGGGACAGUUACUACUUAACCUUGUUGUCUUCAUCUACCUUAGGGCUAAUGAUUUAUUUUUAACAGAGUUUUUCUAAAGAAUGGAGGUAAUCUACAUUAUUUAGCACACUAUACUACCUUCUGUGUUGGAGGUAAUUUAUUACUUAUUUUGACAUUUUACUGGAUUUAAUUCUUAUAUACUAUUUUGGAAUGAAGUUGUCAUUUUUUUUUUCCCAGUCAGGAUCAAUUUUCUUUACCUUUUUUAGGUCAUGGACUUUAGUUAGAUUAUAAUGAAAAAUGUAGACCUAUUCUCCUCCAACAUUUACUUAAAUACAUCAUACAACAUUUUGCCAGUUGUUUCUGGGAUAUAGAGUUUUUGAGGCAUAGGUAUUUGAGGUGUGAACCAUACAAUAUGAACCUUAGCUCAAGAGGACUGGAUUUCAGGCUGGUUGCAGUGACUCACAUCUGUAAUGACAGCCCUUUGGGAGGCCAGGAGGAUUGCUUGAGGCUGGGAGUUUGAGACUCUCCUGGUCAACAUAGCAGUAACCAUCUCUACAAAAAUUUAAAAAUUAGGUGGGUGUGGUGGCACGUACUGGUAGUCCUAGCUACUUGGGAGGCUGAGGCAGUAGGAUUGCUUAAGCCCAGGAAUUUAAGGUUACAGUGGCAAUGAUGGAACCACUGCACUCCAGUCUAGGUGAUGGAGUGAAACCCUGUCUGAAAAAGGAGUACUGGAUUUUGUUUUUUAUCCAUUGAGGAGUUAUUGACCAUCCUUUUUCCCUACUCUGUCCCCAGUAAUCACAACAGUAGCUACAGAAUUUUUCUUUGAAAGGUUUCUGUCAUAUAAGAGAGCUUUAAAAAAUAAUAAUUUGCUAGAAAAUUUUAAAUUAUGGUUGGGCGUGGUGGCUCAUGCCUGUAAUCCCAGUACUUUGGGAGGCUGAGGCAAGAGGAUUGCAUGAGCUCAGGAGUUCGAAACCAGCCUGGGAAACAUAGUGAGACCCUGUCUCUAUUAAAACCAAAAAAAAAAAGAAAAAAUUUUAAAUCAUUACGAACCUUCCCUUCUUCCUUCUUUUUCUUUCUGAAACUAUUGGAAUCCUGACUUAGAAGAAAACUAGUAAAGAGAUAAUUGGUUUUUAUAUCUGCCUUUUUUCCCUCUGAGGGUGGAAAGAUAAGAUGUACUAAAUAAAGUUUAUAGCUAUUUCCUUAUUGUAUGUUUAACAAAUUUUAAAAGUAUAACUCUAUUUAUCCGGGCUUAUUUUAGUUAUUGACUGAAAUUUUUAAAAAAUGGUGGAUUUAGUACAUUCCUUUAAUUUCUUUUCAGUGUCCCACUGAUAUUGUUUAAAGAUUGAAUUAAGUCAUAAUUCUGAAAAGCGGGAACAGAUGUUAUUAUAUUAGUCAAACUACCCUUAAGAGGAACAAAAGGACCUCAUUAGCUCUAUAACUUUAAUGUGUACUUGGGUGUAUGUGGGGAGAGAGGUAAGAAACUACAACUUAGGUGCAUAGAUGGAUCUAAACUUGAAUAGUGUUAGUAGUAUGGCUGCAACCCUGUUACUGUCUCAACAUUUUUGGUCUGCGUUUCCUUCUGUAUCAGCUUUAUUUUCAGCCAAAGAUGACUGUCACUCAAAGGAGAUGGGAAUGGGAUAUUCUAGCCAGACCUAGGUAUAGUGGCCACUCCUGUGGUGACUGGGAAGGCUCACCUCUACCCAAAGCACAUGAAUACAUUCCCCAUAAAAAAGAGGGAUGAUGUUGUUAGCAAAAGGGGUCAGGGAGAAAACAUGUUGAACAGUAAAAUUACAGUUCACAGUCCACUACAGGUACCAUCAGAGGACCAAGAAAUUUUGAAGAAGAUAGAAAGUUCAUGGAAUCGGAUUGACAGCAAAAUCCCAGAGGAAACUGGAACCCAAGAUAACAGAGGUGGAGUCUUUCAUUUUGGAUCAGGAUGAUUUGGAAAAUCCAAUGCUGGAAACAGCUUCCAAGUUGCUCUUAUCAGGUACUGCUGAUGGUGCAGACCUCAGGACAGUAGAUCCAGAAACACAGGCUAGACUGGAAGCUUUACUAGAAGCUGCAGGAAUAGGAAAAUUGUCCACGGCUGAUGGUAAAGCCUUUGCAGAUCCUGAAGUACUUCGGAGGUUGACAUCGUCUGUUAGUUGUGCGUUGGAUGAAGCUGCUGCUGCACUUACCCGUAUGAGAGCUGAAAGCACAGCAAAUGCAGGGCAGUCGGACAACCGCAGUUUGGCAGAAGCCUGUUCAGAAGGAGAUGUAAAUGCUGUGCGAAAGUUACUCAUUGAAGGGCGAAGUGUAAAUGAACACACAGAGGAAGGGGAGAGCCUCCUUUGUUUAGCUUGUUCUGCUGGAUACUAUGAGCUUGCACAGGUUUUGUUGGCAAUGCAUGCAAAUGUGGAAGAUAGGGGAAUCAAAGGUGACAUUACACCUUUAAUGGCUGCUGCUAAUGGAGGACAUGUCAAAAUUGUGAAGUUGCUGCUAGCUCAUAAAGCAGAUGUUAAUGCACAGUCUUCAACAGGCAAUACAGCACUUACAUAUGCUUGUGCUGGAGGCUAUGUAGAUGUUGUAAAGGUGCUCUUGGAAUCCGGUGCUAGUAUUGAGGACCAUAAUGAAAAUGGUCAUACCCCUCUUAUGGAAGCUGGAAGUGCUGGACAUGUGGAAGUAGCCAGAUUGCUGCUAGAAAAUGGGGCUGGCAUUAAUACGCAUUCUAAUGAAUUUAAAGAGAGUGCCCUUACCUUAGCUUGUUACAAAGGACACUUAGAGAUGGUGCGAUUUCUUUUGGAAGCAGGCGCGGAUCAAGAGCAUAAAACAGAUGAAAUGCACACUGCUCUGAUGGAGGCUUGCAUGGAUGGCCAUGUUGAAGUAGCUAGGUUACUUCUUGACAGCGGUGCCCAAGUGAACAUGCCUGCUGAUUCAUUUGAGUCACCAUUAACUUUGGCUGCAUGUGGUGGGCAUGUGGAACUUGCGGCUUUACUUAUUGAAAGAGGAGCUAGCCUGGAAGAGGUCAAUGAUGAAGGUUAUACACCAUUGAUGGAAGCAGCUCGAGAAGGACAUGAAGAAAUGGUGGCAUUACUUCUUGGUCAAGGAGCAAAUAUCAAUGCACAGACAGAAGAAACUCAAGAAACUGCCUUGACUCUGGCUUGCUGUGGAGGCUUUCUGGAAGUGGCAGACUUUCUAAUUAAGGCAGGAGCCGAUAUAGAACUAGGGUGUUCUACCCCUUUAAUGGAAGCUGCUCAAGAGGGUCAUUUGGAGUUAGUUAAAUACUUAUUAGCUGCAGGAGCUAACGUUCAUGCAACAACAGCAACAGGGGAUACAGCACUAACAUAUGCCUGUGAAAAUGGUCAUACUGAUGUAGCAGAUGUCUUACUUCAGGCAGGCGCAGAUCUGGAACAUGAAUCUGAAGGUGGAAGAACUCCUUUAAUGAAAGCUGCAAGAGCUGGUCAUGUUUGUACUGUUCAGUUCUUAAUUAGUAAAGGAGCGAAUGUGAAUAGAACCACAGCUAAUAAUGACCAUACUGUACUGUCCCUGGCUUGUGCAGGGGGUCAUCUGGCAGUGGUGGAACUACUUUUGGCUCAUGGGGCAGAUCCUACUCACCGUUUGAAAGAUGGCUCAACUAUGUUGAUAGAAGCAGCAAAAGGUGGCCAUACAAGUGUUGUUUGCUAUCUCUUGGAUUAUCCUAAUAACUUGCUUUCAGCCCCUCCACCAGAUGUCACUCAGUUAACUCCCCCAUCCCACGAUUUAAAUAGGGCUCCUCGUGUACCAGUUCAAGCACUGCCCAUGGUUGUUCCACCUCAGGAGCCUGACAAACCACCUGCCAAUGUUGCCACCACUCUUCCCAUCAGGAAUAAAGCUGCUUCUAAACAAAAGUCCAGCAGCCAUUUGCCAGCAAACAGCCAGGAUGUACAGGGUUACAUCACCAAUCAGUCUCCAGAGAGCAUUGUAGAAGAGGCUCAGGGAAAGUUAACAGAACUGGAACAGAGGAUAAAAGAAGCCAUAGAAAAGAAUGCACAGCUGCAGUCCUUGGAACUGGCUCAUGCUGACCAACUUACCAAGGAGAAGAUCGAGGAGCUCAACAAAACAAGGGAGGAACAAAUUCAGAAGAAACAAAAGAUUUUGGAGGAACUACAGAAAGUAGAACGAGAGUUACAACUGAAAACUCAGCAGCAGCUAAAAAAGCAGUAUCUAGAGGUUAAAGCUCAAAGAAUUCAACUUCAGCAACAGCAGCAACAGUCUUGCCAACACCUGGGAUUACUAACUCCUGUUGGAGUUGGAGAGCAGCUUUCUGAGGGAGACUAUGCACGGUUACAGCAAGUGGAUCCUGUUUUACUUAAAGAUGAACCCCAGCAGACUGCUGCUCAGAUGGGUUUUGCGCCAAUCCAGCCUCUGGCGAUGCCUCAAGCUUUGCCUCUGGCGGCAGGUCCCUUGCCUCCAGGGUCCAUCGCAAAUCUUACAGAACUGCAAGGAGUGAUAGUUGGACAGCCAGUACUGGGCCAAGCACAGUUGGCAGGGCUGGGGCAAGGAAUUCUGACAGAAACACAACAAGGGUUAAUGGUAGCCAGCCCUGCUCAGACCCUCAAUGACACGCUGGAUGACAUCAUGGCAGCAGUCAGUGGAAGAGCAUCUGCAAUGUCAAACACUCCUACCCACAGUAUUGCUGCAUCCAUUUCCCAACCUCAGACUCCAACUCCAAGUCCUAUCAUCUCUCCUUCAGCCAUGCUUCCUAUCUACCCUGCCAUUGAUAUUGAUGCACAGACUGAGAGUAAUCAUGACACGGCACUAACACUUGCCUGUGCUGGUGGCCACGAGGAACUGGUACAAACACUGCUAGAGAGAGGAGCUAGUAUAGAGCACCGAGACAAGAAAGGUUUUACUCCACUCAUCUUGGCUGCCACAGCUGGUCAUGUUGGUGUUGUGGAAAUAUUGCUGGACAAUGGUGCAGACAUUGAAGCCCAGUCUGAAAGAACCAAGGACACACCACUCUCCUUGGCUUGUUCUGGGGGAAGACAGGAGGUGGUGGAGCUAUUGUUAGCUCGAGGGGCAAAUAAAGAGCACAGGAAUGUUUCUGAUUACACACCUCUAAGUCUGGCUGCUUCUGGUGGCUAUGUGAACAUCAUCAAAAUAUUACUAAAUGCAGGAGCUGAGAUUAACUCUAGAACUGGUAGCAAAUUGGGCAUCUCUCCUCUGAUGUUAGCAGCUAUGAAUGGGCAUACAGCUGCUGUUAAGCUCCUGUUAGACAUGGGCUCUGACAUAAAUGCUCAGAUAGAAACCAAUCGGAACACUGCCCUUACUUUAGCCUGCUUCCAAGGAAGAACUGAAGUGGUUAGUCUUCUGCUUGAUAGAAAAGCAAAUGUUGAACACAGAGCUAAGACUGGUCUCACACCACUAAUGGAAGCUGCCUCUGGUGGAUAUGCGGAGGUGGGCCGAGUUCUUUUGGAUAAAGGUGCUGAUGUUAAUGCCCCUCCAGUUCCCUCCUCAAGAGAUACAGCUUUAACCAUAGCAGCAGAUAAAGGGCAUUACAAAUUCUGUGAGCUUCUUAUUGGCAGGGGAGCUCAUAUUGAUGUACGUAACAAGAAGGGGAACACUCCAUUGUGGCUAGCAGCAAAUGGUGGACACCUCGAUGUGGUUCAGUUACUGGUGCAAGCAGGUGCAGAUGUGGAUGCAGCAGAUAACCGCAAGAUAACUCCUCUUAUGGCAGCAUUUAGAAAGGGUCAUGUGAAGGUGGUGCGCUACUUAGUCAAAGAAGUCAAUCAGUUUCCAUCAGAUUCUGAAUGUAUGAGAUACAUAGCAACCAUCACUGAUAAGGAGAUGCUGAAGAAGUGUCAUCUUUGUAUGGAGUCAAUAGUACAAGCCAAAGAUAGACAGGCUGCUGAAGCAAACAAAAACGCCAGCAUUUUGUUAGAGGAGUUAGACUUGGAAAAGUUAAGGGAAGAAAGUCGGAGGCUGGCUUUGGCUGCGAAAAGAGAAAAAAGAAAAGAGAAGAGAAGGAAGAAAAAGGAAGAACAAAGAAGGAAACUAGAAGAAAUUGAAGCCAAAAAUAAAGAGAACUUUGAACUCCAAGCUGCUCAAGAAAAAGAAAAGCUUAAAGUUGAAGAUGAGCCUGAAGUCUUGACAGAACCUCCAAGUGCCACAACCACUACUACCAUAGGUAUAUCUGCAACCUGGACAACUUUGGCAGGUUCUCAUGGUAAAAGAAAUAAUACCAUAACUACAACCAGUUCAAAGAGGAAAAACAGGAAAAAUAAAAUUACUCCAGAAAACGUUCAAAUUAUAUUUGAUGAUCCACUACCAAUUUCAUACAGUCAGCCAGAGAAGGUGAAUGGAGAGUCCAAGAGCAGCAGUACCAGCGAGAGUGGGGACAGUGAUAACAUGAGGAUUUCCAGCUGCAGCGAUGAAAGUAGUAACAGCAACAGCAGUCGUAAGAGUGACAAUCAUUCACCAGCUGUGGUCACUACCACUGUGAGCAGCAAAAAGCAGCCAUCAGUUCUUGUUACAUUUCCAAAGGAAGAGAGAAAAUCUGUUUCUGGCAAGGCUUCAAUAAAAUUGUCAGAAACUAUCAGUGAAGGGACCAGUAAUUCUCUAUCUACUUGUACAAAAUCUGGUCCAUCUCCCCUUUCUUCUCCAAAUGGGAAGUUAACAGUAGCAAGUCCUAAGCGUGGGCAAAAGAGGGAAGAAGGAUGGAAAGAAGUUGUAAGAAGGUCAAAGAAAGUAUCUGUUCCAUCAACUGUGAUAUCCAGAGUGAUUGGAAGAGGAGGCUGUAAUAUCAAUGCUAUUCGGGAGUUUACUGGUGCACACAUAGAUAUUGAUAAACAGAAAGACAAGACUGGAGACCGGAUAAUCACUAUAAGGGGUGGCACUGAAUCAACAAGACAAGCAACUCAAUUGAUUAAUGCUUUGAUCAAGGAUCCAGACAAAGAAAUUGAUGAACUUAUUCCAAAGAAUCGUUUGAAAAGCUCCUCAGCAAAUUCCAAAAUAGGGUCAUCAGCACCUACCACCACUGCUGCUAACACUUCCUUAAUGGGAAUUAAAAUGACAACUGUAGCUCUGUCAUCAACAUCUCAAACUGCCACAGCACUCACUGUGCCUGCAAUUUCUUCUGCAUCCACUCACAAAACCAUUAAGAACCCAGUGAAUAAUGUGAGGCCUGGUUUUCCAGUUUCUCUUCCAUUAGCAUAUCCUCCUCCACAGUUUGCACAUGCUUUGCUUGCUGCUCAGACUUUCCAGCAGAUCCGUCCACCAAGGUUGCCCAUGACCCACUUUGGAGGUACUUUUCCACCAGCUCAAUCCACUUGGGGUCCGUUUCCUGUCAGGCCUUUGAGCCCUGCCAGAGCUACUAACUCGCCUAAGCCUCACAUGGUGCCUCGCCAUAGCAAUCAGAAUAGCAGUGGUUCUCAGGUGAAUUCAGCAGGUUCUUUAACUUCAAGCCCAACAACUACAACCAGUUCAUCAGCUUCAACGGUGCCUGGUACAUCUACAAAUGGCAGUCCAAGUUCACCUUCUGUCCGAAGGCAGCUUUUUGUCACAGUUGUGAAGACAUCCAAUGCCACCACAACAACAGUCACAACCACGGCAAGCAACAACAACACUGCACCCACAAAUGCCACAUAUCCUAUGCCUACUGCCAAAGAACACUAUCCAGUAUCAUCCCCAUCUUCCCCAUCACCACCAGCCCAGCCAGGAGGGGUUUCUAGAAACAGCCCUUUGGAUUGUGGAUCAGCAUCUCCAAAUAAAGUGGCAUCUUCCUCCGAACAGGAAGCAGGUAGUCCACCAGUAGUAGAAACAACAAACACUAGACCUCCAAACAGCAGCAGUUCUUCUGGGAGUUCAUCAGCUCAUUCUAAUCAGCAACAACCUCCGGGAUCUGUUUCUCAGGAACCAAGACCACCUCUUCAGCAGUCUCAGGUUCCUCCCCCGGAAGUUAGAAUGACUGUUCCUCCUUUAGCAACAAGUUCUGCUCCAGUGGCGGUGCCUUCUACUGCCCCAGUGACUUACCCUAUGCCUCAGACACCAAUGGGAUGCCCCCAGCCUACUCCUAAAAUGGAAACCCCUGCUAUUAGACCACCCCCUCAUGGCACAACUGCCCCUCACAAGAAUUCAGCUUCAGUGCAAAAUUCAUCUGUUGCAGUCCUCAGUGUCAAUCACAUUAAAAGACCUCACAGUGUUCCCUCUUCUGUCCAGCUACCUUCGACCUUAAGUACACAAAGUGCUUGUCAGAAUUCAGUACAUCCAGCAAAUAAGCCUAUUGCUCCCAAUUUCAGUGCCCCCUUACCAUUUGGGCCCUUUAGCACAUUGUUUGAAAACAGCCCUACUUCUGCUCAUGCCUUCUGGGGAGGAUCUGUUGUUUCAUCUCAGUCAACACCAGAAUCUAUGCUAUCAGGAAAAUCCUCAUAUUUGCCAAAUUCAGAUCCUUUACAUCAGUCUGAUACUUCCAAAGCUCCAGGUUUUAGACCACCAUUACAGAGACCUGCUCCAAGUCCCUCAGGUAUUGUCAAUAUGGACUCGCCAUAUGGUUCUGUAACACCUUCUUCAACACAUUUGGGAAACUUUGCUUCAAACAUUUCAGGAGGUCAGAUGUACGGACCUGGGGCACCCCUUGGAGGAGCACCCGCAGCUGCUAACUUUAACAGACAACAUUUUUCCCCGCUUAGUUUGUUGACUCCGUGUUCAUCAGCAUCAAAUGAUUCUUCUGCACAGUCAGUAUCCUCGGGAGUUCGUGCACCAUCUCCUGCCCCAUCAUCAGUACCGUUAGGGUCAGAAAAGCCCAGCAAUGUGUCUCAGGACAGGAAAGUUCCAGUCCCUAUUGGGACUGAACGUUCUGCACGUAUCAGGCAAACUGGAACGUCAGCUCCAUCUGUUAUUGGGAGCAAUUUGUCUACAUCAGUAGGACAUAGUGGCAUCUGGUCCUUUGAAGGGAUUGGUGGCAAUCAAGACAAAGUAGACUGGUGUAACCCUGGGAUGGGAAAUCCUAUGAUCCACAGACCGAUGUCUGACCCAGGAGUAUUUUCACAACAUCAAGCAAUGGAGCGAGAUAGUACAGGAAUUGUAACUCCUUCUGGUACAUUCCAUCAGCAUGUUCCUGCAGGCUACAUGGACUUUCCUAAAGUUGGGGGUAUGCCUUUUUCUGUGUAUGGGAAUGCAAUGAUUCCUCCAGUAGCACCUAUCCCUGAUGGUGCUGGAGGACCCAUAUUUAAUGGCCCUCAUGCUGCAGACCCUUCUUGGAACUCACUGAUAAAGAUGGUUUCCAGCUCCACGGAAAAUAAUGGCCCUCAAACGGUGUGGACUGGACCCUGGGCACCUCACAUGAACAGUGUGCAUAUGAACCAGCUUGGCUGAUGAGGAUCAGCUUGUUAGCCUGCAGAUUCCUUUUCAUUUGGAGGAAAUCACAAGUGGCCGAAAAAAAAAAUUAUGCUCCCAAAUCAUUCUACUGAUGUGCUUGACUGAAGUGUGUAGGCUUUUUGCAGAAGAUCUUACUAACUGACCUAUUUUCUGUGAACAUUUGUGACUGCCCAUUCCCCAUCAUCAUCCGUUUUACCUUAGUUAGCAUUUUUCUUAUCAUUUUUCUUUUUUUCUUUCCCUCUUCCCCUUUGGACAUAACUUUCUGUUGAAGCUGUUCUUUGGCUGGUUGGUUUUAGUACUGUAAACUGCUUCUGAGCAAACACGGAAAUUUAGCAAAAUUAUGUAAACUUGAUCCUGAAGUUUUAGAAUGGCAAAUAAAUGUACAAUUGUUUACAUAACAGAAAAGGCUAAGCAGAAAGUAAAUUUCAAUAUGUCAGUAUAGAGGCUCUACUUUAUGUAGACUUAAAUUAAUGUGAGAUAUGUACCUUCAUAUUCAGAAAUCUGGAUGUUUCCUUCAUACAUUAAACUAUUAAUAAGCAUAACUUUUCUACUGGUGUAAUUUAAGUAUAAAGUAAAAUAAUGGGCAUUAUCAUUGGAUGUUUCCCCACAUUGGCUUUUAAAAUACCCAUCUUGCUUUCUUUUUGGUUUAUUUGUAGCAAGGCACAUAUAGAAGAAGAAAUUUCUGGCUUUUCCAUGUUGUUUUAUUACCUUUUCUCACUUUUAAAACUAAUACAGACUUAUCUCCUCACUCCUUUUUCUCUCCUUACCUUUACCACUAAUACCAGUAAAAUUAUCUUUCUGAUAGUGAAAAGGUUCUGUCAAGAUUUUCACUGUAAUGGCUGCUACAGAGAUGGACCAUCUUCAUCAUCACCAGUGGUUUCUUCUAAUUAUAAAAUGUUUAAACUUUCUGAGAAUUUAAAAAGCCACCACUGUUCCCAGUCAGCAUAUACAAGCUCUUAAUAUUCUGUUUAUUAAAUAAUUCAAUGUACUAUUUUAUAUUGGAUGAUAUUGAUUCUUAACAUUGGCUUUUCAGUCAUCAACAGUCAACAUAAAAAUUUCAAUUUUCAGUAAUUUAGUGGAAAAUAUCUUAUUUCUUUUUUCAAUUUUAAAGGCUUCCUGCUUUUUUACCCUUGUAUAUUAUCAGUGAAAAGGAUCAACAGUUAAUUUGAGCCAAGUAAUAAAAGAAAUUCUGCAUUUGUCACGAAGACAAUUUAUGGUAGACAGAUAAAUACACAGAUUACAGUGUAAAGUCUCCAUUUAACCUGUUUAUAAAAGAUACAAGGCCACACUAAACUACUCAGUGGGAUUUAUAUAUUCCAUCCACUUGAAACAAUAAACAGUAAUGUAUCCAAGAAGAUUAUGUGUCCUACCCUGUCUCAUGGAAAAAUUAAUUAUAUGGUUGAAAUGUAAAAGAAAGUAAGCAUAAAAAUCGAGUAAUGUAUAUAUCAAUUUGUCUUCUUUUUUUUUAAUUAGACAUAAAAUUUCACACUGGUAAAACAUAAAAACUAACUAAAAUUCAUAUAAAUCACCUAGAGUUGAUGAUAUUAACAUGGUUCCUUGGUUGUCAAGUAAAUCAAAUGAUUUCUUCCAUCUGAGUAAAGAGUAAAGCCUGAGUAAAGAGUAAAAAGAUGACUUCUCAAACAUAUCCAGAAAUUUGUAAACAGUACACUCAUAUCUUUUAGUUUAAGAAGUGGUCUUAAAAUAUAUAAAUUUGUUUUUCCACCUAUGUUUAAUAUGCCCAAAUUUAAAGGGAGAGCUAAAAGACAGCCUACAAAUAAAUAUAGCUAUGAAAUAAAAUUAUAGCACUUUACUAAAAAAGGGAUGUAAUAAUGUUAUUUAACGAAGUAUUUUAUAUAUGACUUGCCACUAUUCUAUACAUAAAAUUUUUUUUCUUAAUUCUUUCCUGUGUUAACUAGGGUUAUUUUCUAUUUAAGGUAAUCCUGCUGGAGAACAGAUGCUAUCCAAUAUUUAUUACAACACAUGAGUUGUGUUGUUUCACAAUACUGAAUUUCUUAGGUGAGGUAUUUUAUUUAAAAAGGAGGGGGAAAACUCCUAUAUUUUCUUGACUUCAAACCUGUGGGGCCAGGGGAUAUAGAUUGAAAUGCUCCGUAUUUAGUCUUGGGGAUCAGGCUUGUUUAGUACAAUACCAUGGUUUUAGAAGUCUGUACUAGGAACAUUUUUAAAAUACAUUUUUUAUAUUUCAGAUGUAAUGCAGUGCACUUUUAUUUGAACAAUAAAAAAACCCAUAACUUUUUGAGACCAUGAAGGUCUUUUAUUUUUUAAUUUUGAAAAUAUGUGGUAUGUGUAUAUGCAGACUACAUCAUUGUUUUAAGAAAUGAUUUAACUCUUGGACAUUACACUUGGGUUAGUUCACACCUUAAAUCCCCAAGUAGUUAAUAUCUCAAUUAUUGUAUAAUCAGUUUAUACCAUCCAUUCCCAACAAAAUUCCACAUUUCAUGCCUUUUCAACAUACAUUUCAACAUAAUCAACAUAUUUACAAACACUGACUUCACUGUUUAUAAAGAAGAAAUUUCCCCUCCUAUUUCCCAUUACUGAAAAGUCAAGUCAUUUUUAUUGAUACAUGAAAAUUAAUUUUUUUGUAAAUGACUACGUAUAGUCAUUUUUCUCCUUUGGAAAAGGUAAAUAGCUUAUUAACUAAUCCUGUCUUGUUCUUCACAAAAAUAAUAGUCCAUCCGUGUUUUGACUCAAAUAACCUAAAUACACAUUUUGUAAAAAUUUUGUACCCUAUAUUACUUAUUUUUAAAACAGUACAGUGUUAGACUAAACAGGAAAACUCAAAGUUAUAAAAUCUCUUCAGAUCCUCUAGUUUAUUAAAUCUAUUUUCAUGUUGA